GGAAGUGACGCGAGGCGUAGCGGAAGUUACUGCAGCCGCGGUGUUGUGCUGUGGGGAAGGGAGAAGGAUUUGUAAACCCCGGAGCGAGGUUCUGCUUACCCGAGGCCGCUGCUGUGCGGAGACCCCCGGGUGAAGCCACCGUCAUCAUGUCUGACCAGGAGGCAAAACCUUCAACUGAGGACUUGGGGGAUAAGAAGGAAGGUGAAUAUAUUAAACUCAAAGUCAUUGGACAGGAUAGCAGUGAGAUUCACUUCAAAGUGAAAAUGACAACACAUCUCAAGAAACUCAAAGAAUCAUACUGUCAAAGACAGGGUGUUCCAAUGAAUUCACUCAGGUUUCUCUUUGAGGGUCAGAGAAUUGCUGAUAAUCAUACUCCAAAAGAAGCACAGUGGCCCACGCCUGCAAUCCUAGCACUUUGGGAGGCUGAGGCGGGCUGGAUCACUGCAGGUCAGGAGUUGAGACCAGCCUGGGCAACAUGGCGAAACCUCAUCUCUACUAAAAAUAGAAAAAGUAGCCAGCUGGGAAUGGAGGAAGAAGAUGUGAUUGAAGUUUAUCAGGAACAAACGGGGGGUCAUUCAACAGUUUAGAUAUUCUUUUUAUUUUUUUUCUUUUCCCUCAAUCCUUUUUUAUUUUUAAAAAUAGUUCUUUUGUAAUGUGGUGUUCAAAACGGAAUUGAAAACUGGCACCCCAUCUCUUUGAAACAUCUGGUAAUUUGAAUUCUAGUGCUCAUUAUUCAUUAUUGUUUGUUUUCAUUGUGCUGAUUUUUGGUGAUCAAGCCUCAGUCCCCUUCAUAUUACCCUCUCCUUUUUAAAAAUUACGUGUGCACAGAGAGGUCACCUUUUUCAGGACAUUGCAUUUUCAGGCUUGUGGUGAUAAAUAAGAUCGACCAAUGCAAGUGUUCAUAAUGACUUUCCAAUUGGCCCUGAUGUUCUAGCAUGUGAUUACUUCACUCCUGGACUGUGACUUUCAGUGGGAGAUGGAAGUUUUUCAGAGAACUGAACUGUGGAAAAAUGACCUUUCCUUAACUUGAAGCUACUUUUAAAAUUUGAGGGUCUGGACCAAAAGAAGAGGAAUAUCAGGUUGAAGUCAAGAUGACAGAUAAGGUGAGAGUAAUGACUAACUCCAAAGAUGGCUUCACUGAAGAAAAGGCAUUUUAAGAUUUUUUAAAAAUCUUGUCAGAAGAUCCCAGAAAAGUUCUAAUUUUCAUUAGCAAUUAAUAAAGCUAUACAUGCAGAAAUGAAUACAACAGAACACUGCUCUUUUUGAUUUUAUUUGUACUUUUUGGCCUGGGAUAUGGGUUUUAAAUGGACAUUGUCUGUACCAGCUUCAUUAAAAUAAACAAUAUUUGUAAAAAUCAUACUAAUGCUUAUUUUAUUUUAAUUGUAUAGAAAGAAAAAAAUGCCUAAAAUAAGGUUUUCUUGCAUAAAUACUGGAAAUUGCACAUGGUACAAAUUUUUUCUUCAUUACUGUACAGUGAUGAUGUUAAUGACUUUGAAGCACUGAAAGUUACUGAAGUGCCUUCUGAAUCAAGGAUUUAAUUAAGGCCACAAUACCUUUUUAAUACUCAGUGUUCUGUUUUUUUAAAAACUUGAUAUUCCUGUAUGGUGCAUAUAUGAUACAGUUACCUAAUCAUGUUGAAUAAAUGGGCAUGCCAAAAAUUCUUACUGGA